AUACAAGAAUGGCUAAGCAAACUAGUGUACAUCAACCUGGAGGAAUAUUAUAUAGUCUUUUAAAAUAACAAAUAUGUAGAUUGUUAAUACAUGGGAAAAGGUAUAUGAAAUAGGUGGAACCAAGCAGAACAUAAUAUAGCAUAUUUCCUACUGAUUACAACUAUGGCAAAAUGUAUGUAAAUGCUUCAGUGAAUUUGGAGAGUGGAGGUAGUAUUGUUAGUGUCUUUUUUUUUUUGAGACGGAGUCUUGCUGUGUUGCCCAGGCUGGAGUGCAGUGGCGUGAUCUCACCUCACUGCAGCCUCCGCUUCCCGGGUUCAAGCAAUUCUCCUGUCUCAGCCUCCCAAGUAGCUGGGAUUACAGGUGUGCACCACCACGCCCGGCUAAUUUUUGCAUUUUUAGUAGAUGAGGUUUCACCAUAUUGGUCAGUUAGUGUCCUUUUUUUUAUUGUAGUAAAAUAUAUACUCACUAUUUUAACCAUAAAAGCUUAUGUUCACUGGCAUUACAUACAUUUACAAUGUUGUGCAACCAUAACCAGGGUCCAUUUCCACAACCUGAAUUUCAUCAUCUCAAACAGAGACUGUGUAUCCAUUAAACAAUAACUCCUACUCCCCCUCCUCCUCCUAAGCCCUUGGUAAAGUCUAUUCUAUUUUUUUGUCCCUAUGAAUUUGCCUAUUCUAGAUACCUCAAGAAAAACAGAAUAUUUGUCCUUUUGUCUUGCUUACUUAACUCAGCAUCAUCUGUAUUGGAGUGUGUGUCAGAAUUGCCUUCCUUUUGAAGACUGAAUAGUAUUCCACAGUAUGGAUGUGCUGCAUUUGUUUAUCCGUUUCUCCAUUCGUGGAUGCUCGGGUUGCUCCCACCUUUUGGCUAUUGUGAAAAAUGCUUCAAGUCCCUGCUUUCGGUUCUUUGUUGGUAUAUACCUAGGAGUGGAACUGCUGGGUCAUAUGGUAAUUCUAUGUUUCACUUUUUGAGGAACUGCCAACCUUUUAGUGUCUUUUUAUUUUUUUUAAUUUUUAUUUUUAUUUAUUUAUUUUUUGAGAUGGAGUCUCACUCUUUCGCCCAGGCUGGACUGCAGUGGCGCUAUCUCGGCUCACUGCAAGGUCUGCCUCCCAGGUUCACACCAUUCUCCUGCCUCAGCCUCCCGAGUAGCUGGGACUACAGGCACUCGCCACCAAGCCCGGCCAGCGUCCCAUGCUCGGUGGCCCCAGAAAAGUCAGUGUGUAGGCCUCAGCCACUUCAGGUCCGGCGUACAUUCUCCCUGGACACCAUCCUCAGCUCCUACCUUCUGGGCCAGUGGCCACGAGAUGCUGAUGGGGCCUUCACCUGCUGCACCAAUGACAAGGCCACCCAGACGCCCCUGUCCUGGCAAGAGCUAGAAGGUGAGCGUGCCAGUUCCUGUGCACACAAGCGCUCAGCAUCCUGGGGCAGCACAGACCACCGAAAAGAGAUUUCCAAGUUGAAGCAACAACUGCAGAGGACGAAGCUGAGCCGCAGUGGGAAAGAGAAGGAGCGAGGUUCACCACUCCUAGGGGACCACGCAGUGCGGGGAGCACUGAGGGCGUCCCCUCCCAGCUUCCCCUCAGGGUCCCCUGUCUUGCGACUCAGCCCCUGCCUGCACAGGAGCCUGGAAGGGCUCAACCAAGAGCUGGAGGAGGUAUUUGUGAAGGAGCAGGGAGAAGAGGAGCUGCUGAGGAUCCUUGAUAUCCCUGAUGGGCACCGGGCCCCAGCUCCUCCCCAGAGUGGCAGCUGUGAUCAUCCCCUCCUCCUCCUGGAGCCUGGCAACCUUGCCAGCUCUCCUUCCAUGUCCUUGGCAUCUCCCCAGCCUUGUGGCCUGGCCAGUCAUGAGGAACAUCGGGGUGCCGCCGAGGAGCUGGCAUCCACCCCCAACGACAAAGCCUCCUCUCCAGGACACCCAGCCUUUCUUGAAGAUGGCAGCCCAUCUCCAGUCCUUGCCUUUGCUGCCUCCCCUCGACCUAAUCAUAGCUACAUCUUCAAACGGGAGCCCCCAGAAGGCUGUGAGAAAGUGCGUGUGUUUGAAGAAGCCACGUCUCCAGGUCCUGACCUGGCCUUCCUGACUUCCUGUCCUGACAAGAACAAAGUCCAUUUCAACCCGACUGGCUCAGCCUUCUGCCCCGUCAACCUGAUGAAGCCCCUCUUCCCCGGCAUGGGCUUCAUCUUCCGUAACUGCCCCUCAAACCCGGGAUCUCCCCUUCCCCCGGCCAGCCCCAGGCCACCACCUCGGAAGGAUCCGGAAGCCUCCAAGGCCUCCCCACUGCCAUUCGAGCCAUGGCAGCGCACCCCACCAUCAGAAGAGCCUGUGCUUUUCCAGAGCUCCCUGAUGGUCUGAGGGUCCCACCCCUGCCCCACUUUACCAUAGAGACCAGUGCCUUGGUGGCAGGUCCCUCCCCAGGUCCCCUGAGAUGGGGUAUGGAGGGGCCCUUCCCUCUCGGCCUUCGAGCACUUUCUUUCACUUACUGUGUCAAAGCCCUGGGUCCUCUUUUUGAUGGGCACCGGCCCCUCUGAACGUGAUGGGACCUGCCUUCUCCACUAGUAGCUGGGCAGCUCACAAUUCACACCUGUGUACCUGCCACAUCCCUCACUUGGUGGAAAACACCCAGAAGGUCUUGAGUCCCCCACCCCUGGGUGUCAGUCCAAAUGACUGUAUAGGAGGCCCUUAUUUUUGUCACAGAGCAAGCUGGCCAUGAACGAAGGAGAGAAGACGCCACAGAUUUCCUUCCCUCUCCUCCAGGAGACCAUAAGAUAGAUCCCCCAUCCUCUCAGCCCUAUUCCCAUGCCUCCCUCUCAUUGGAGGAGCUGACCAAAGCAGCCCUAACGGGCCAUAACACUUGACCAAUUCAGCUGCUGGCAGAGGGAGGAAACAAGUGUUUUCCCAAGUGGCAUUUUCAUCUCGCUUUCACCCUGACUAAAGAUUGUCUUAAGUAGCAGCCCAGCCCGCCCAGCCCCAGGUGGGUAGUGGGGAGGAGAGCUGGCAUUCCUCCAGGUGGCAAAUGGCGACUCUAUACUCUCCGCCCGCCCCAGGGCUGGAUGGAUUAGAAAAAUGCCUAUUUUUCUUGUAUCGAUGUAGAGACUCUAUUUUCUCCCAAAGACACUAUUUUUGCAGCUGUUUGAAGUUUGUAUAUUUUCCGUACUGCAGAGCUUACACAAAAUUGAAGAAUGUUAAUGUUCGAGUUUUCUUAUCUUGUGUUUAGAGGUUGUUUUUUGCAGAUCUUGGUGUUAAUAGACCAAAUAAAUAAAUAAAUAUUCCCAGCA